AGGCGGGAAUUCGUCUCGGGUUGUGUGGUUGAGGGGUCUGGUGGGUCGAGGAAAGGUAACGGCGGCCCCAGUCCUGCACACAAGGCCGGGGAAGUAGCAGCACCCCCAGGAAGAGGGAGGAGGAAGGGCUCGUGCCCUUUCUUCUCUUCCAGGGCUCCGCUUUAUUUGCUCUCAGAAGUCGGUUUCCUUUCCUUUUCUUCAGUGAAUCGGAGCUCAGAGCGUUGCUUCGGUUUCCCUCCAGACAGGCAAGUCGGAGGGAAGUCCACGGAAAGGGCUUGAGUUCUUCUGCACAGCCUGCGGGCCCAUGGGUGGUGACUGGAUCACCAGGGUCUCGGGGAUCUCAACUGGCUGGGGGAGGAGGGAGAUACGGGGCAGAAAACCUGAGGAGGGAGCCUAUCCUUACCUCCUUUGAGCGCAGGCCUGUUCUUAGCCCGGGCGCUGCGUUAAUUCUUGGCGGGAGGCAGAGGGGUGUGUUUAUCCUUUAUGCAAUGUUUGGGGGAAGCUACCCCAUUUUGACACUAUUGUUGCCACAGCCGGGGUACAGGACGGGCUGAUUUCUAGAUUAUAUCUGAGUAACUAGGCCAGCGUUGAGUUGUUGAUUCAUAUUAAGAGGUUAGAUUCCACCAUACCUCAUUCUCAGAGCUUUACAGAUAGAAUCGCAAAAUGUUAGAGCUGGAAAAUACCCUAGAAUAAUGGUUCUUCUUUUGGAGCACACAAGCAGUGGUGAAUGUUAUUAUUGGCUUCAUAAUCUAUUGAAUUGCUAUUUUAACCAUCUCUUCGUCCCCAGGUUGAAUUUACAAUUUUUUCCCACGACUGCAAAUAAUUCCUUAUUUAAUAACAGUGCAUGUAAUUUCCCCCGCUAUUUUGAUUUCCUUGAGAUAUAUUUACGGGAAGAGAAAUCUAUGGACUUUUUCUUCAGAAAAAUGCAAUCAUGUACAGAAACUUAUGCUUGCAAUUUCAAGAGGUCAUUGUCUCUGAAUUACAUCCGUGGAUCCUAGGUUAAGAAAAGUGGUUUAGAAGAGGUGAGGAUUAAAGUGAUCCUCAUCUGUAUCAGAUCCUGGGUUAGGUACAUUCUGCCCUGGCUAAUUUUCAUAAAAACCCUGUCAGGUAAGUAGUAGUAUUUCAAUUCCAUAUAUGGAGAAACAAGCUCUGAGAAGUUAAGUGAUUCACACAGUGGAAUUCAAACUUAGGAUUGCCUUACUCCAAAGCCCAUCCUGUUUCUAUAAUACUCUACUGAUCUUCAAAUAACAUUUUUGAGUGCCUACUAUGUGCCAAGGCAUUCUCUUUCUUAUAACAGCCUUUAAAUUAAAUUAGGGGUUAUCACAGGUAAGGAUCUUAGACUAGAGAAGUAAAAAGAUAUGUCAAAGAUAACAUACCUGAGUCAAAGAUAACAUACCAGGCAGUAUACCAAAACCUGGUAUAGAACCUAUGCUUCCUGACUUCUGGUCAACAGCUUUUUUCUUCUAACUGGAGGACUGCAGAAAGGGGUAACACAAAGGGGAAGAACUGGAGAAAGAGUGAUGCUACGGAGUUGUAGAGAGAGAGGCCUCAGGAACUUAUUUGUUUCUGUAGGUUGAUUACAUCUGAUCUAACUGUUACAAGAGCUCAUGUUUAAUCUGUUAGGAAUCUGAAAUAAACAGGAAAGCACUAUGUCUUCAAUGUGGUCUGAAUAUACAAUUGGUGGGGUGAAGAUUUACUUUCCUUAUAAAGCUUACCCGUCACAGCUUGCUAUGAUGAAUUCUAUUCUCAGAGGAUUAAACAGCAAGCAACAUUGUUUGUUGGAGAGUCCCACAGGAAGUGGAAAAAGCUUAGCCUUACUUUGUUCUGCUUUAGCAUGGCAACAAUCUCUUAGUGGGAAACCAGCAGAUGAGGGCGUAAGUGAAAAAGCUGAAGUACAAUUGUCAUGUUGUUGUGCAUGCCAUUCAAAGGAUUUUACAAACAAUGACAUGAACCAAGGAACUUCACGUCAUUUCAACUAUCCAAGCACACCACCUUCUGAAAGAAAUGGCACUUCAUCAACUUGUCAAGACUCCCCUGAAAAAACCACUCUGGCUGCAAAGUUAUCUGCUAAGAAACAGGCAUCCAUAUACAGAGAUGAAAAUGAUGAUUUUCAAGUAGAGAAGAAAAGAAUUCGACCCUUAGAAACUACACAGCAGAUUAGAAAACGUCAUUGCUUUGGAACAGAAGUACACAAUUUGGAUGCAAAAGUUGAUUCAGGAAAGACUGUAAAACUCAACUCUCCACUGGAAAAGAUAAACUCCUUUUCGCCACAGAAACCCCCUGGCCACUGUUCUAGGUGCUGUUGUUCUACUAAACAAGGAAACAGUCAAGAGUCAUCGAAUACCAUUAAGAAGGAUCAUACAGGGAAAUCCAAGAUACCCAAAAUAUAUUUUGGGACACGCACACACAAGCAGAUUGCUCAGAUUACUAGAGAGCUCCGGAGGACGGCAUAUUCAGGGGUUCCAAUGACUAUUCUUUCCAGCAGGGAUCAUACUUGUGUCCAUCCUGAGGUAGUCGGUAACUUCAACAGAAAUGAGAAGUGCAUGGAAUUGCUAGAUGGGAAAAACGGAAAAUCCUGCUAUUUUUAUCAUGGAGUUCAUAAAAUUAGUGAUCAGCACACAUUACAGACUUUCCAAGGGAUGUGCAAAGCCUGGGAUAUAGAAGAACUUGUCAGCCUGGGGAAGAAACUAAAGGCCUGUCCAUAUUACACAGCCCGAGAACUAAUACAAGAUGCUGACAUCAUAUUUUGUCCCUACAACUAUCUUCUAGAUGCACAAAUAAGGGAAAGUAUGGAUUUAAAUCUGAAAGAACAGGUUGUCAUUUUAGAUGAAGCUCAUAACAUCGAGGACUGUGCUCGGGAAUCAGCAAGUUACAGUGUAACAGAAGUUCAGCUUCGGUUUGCUCGGGAUGAACUAGAUAGUAUGGUCAACAAUAAUAUAAGGAAGAAAGAUCAUGAACCCCUACGAGCUGUGUGCUGUAGCCUCAUUAAUUGGUUAGAAGCAAACGCUGAAUAUCUUGUAGAAAGAGAUUAUGAAUCAGCUUGUAAAAUAUGGAGUGGAAAUGAAAUGCUCUUAACUUUACACAAAAUGGGUAUCACCACUGCUACUUUUCCCAUUUUGCAGGGACAUUUUUCUGCUGUUCUUCAAAAAGAGGAAAAAAUCUCACCAAUUUAUGGUAAAGAGGAGGCAAGAGAAGUACCUGUUAUUAGUGCAUCAACUCAAAUAAUGCUUAAAGGACUUUUUAUGGUACUUGACUAUCUUUUUAGGCAAAAUAGCAGAUUUGCAGAUGAUUAUAAAAUUGCGAUUCAACAGACUUACUCCUGGACAAAUCAGAUUGAUAUUUCAGACAAAAAUGGGUUGUUGGUUCUACCAAAAAAUAAGAAACGUUCACGACAGAAAACUGCAGUUCAUGUGCUAAACUUUUGGUGCUUAAAUCCAGCUGUGGCCUUUUCAGAUAUUAAUGGCAAAGUUCAGACCAUUGUUUUGACAUCUGGUACAUUAUCACCAAUGAAAUCCUUUUCGUCAGAACUUGGUGUUACAUUUACUAUCCAGCUGGAGGCUAAUCAUAUCAUUAAAAAUUCACAGAUAAUGUCUUCAAAGUUCAUCAUCUAUGUUGUAGCAUGUGCCAGAGUUUCCUCUUUAAAGGUUUGGGUUGGUACCAUUGGGUCAGGCCCCAAGGGUCGGAAUCUCUGUGCUACCUUCCAGAAUACUGAAACAUUUGAGUUCCAAGAUGAAGUGGGAGCACUUUUGUUAUCUGUGUGCCAGACUGUGAGCCAAGGAAUUUUGUGUUUCUUGCCAUCUUACAAGUUAUUAGAAAAAUUAAAAGAACGUUGGCUCUCUACUGGUUUAUGGCAUAAUCUGGAGUUGGUGAAGACAGUCAUUGUAGAACCACAGGGAGGAGAAAAAACAAAUUUUGAUGAAUUACUGCAGGUGUACUAUGACGCAAUCAAAUACAAAGGAGAGAAAGAUGGAGCUCUCCUGGUAGCAGUUUGUCGUGGUAAAGUGAGUGAGGGUCUGGAUUUCUCAGAUGACAAUGCCCGUGCUGUCAUAACAAUAGGAAUUCCUUUUCCAAAUGUGAAAGAUCUACAGGUUGAACUAAAACGACAAUACAAUGACCACCAUUCAAAAUUGAGAGGUCUUCUACCUGGCCGUCAGUGGUAUGAAAUUCAAGCAUACAGGGCCUUAAACCAGGCCCUUGGUAGAUGUAUUAGACACAGAAAUGAUUGGGGAGCUCUUAUUCUAGUGGAUGAUCGCUUUAGGAAUAACCCAAGUCGCUAUAUAUCUGGACUUUCUAAAUGGGUACGGCAGCAGAUUCAGCACCAUUCAACCUUUGAAAGUGCACUGGAAUCCUUGGCUGAAUUUUCCAAAAAGCAUCAAAAAGUUCUUAAUGUAUCCAUAAAGGACAGAACCAAUAUACAGGACAAUGAGUCUACACUUGAAGUGACCUCUUUAAAGUACAGUACCUCACCUUAUUUACUGGAAGCAGCAAGUCAUCUAUCACCAGAAAAUUUUGUGGAAGAUGAAGCAAAGAUAUGUGUCCAGGAACUACAGUGUCCUAAAAUUAUUACCAAAAAUUCACCUCUACCAAGUAGCAUUAUCUCCAGAAAGGAGAAAAAUGAUCCAGUAUUCCUGGAAGAAGCAGGGAAAGCAGAAAAAAUUGUGAUUUCCAGAUCCACAAGCCCAACUUUCAACAAACAAACAAAGAGAGUUAGCUGGUCAAGCUUUAAUUCUUUGGGACAGUAUUUUACUGGUAAAAUACCGAAGGCAACACCUGAGCUCGGGUCAUCAGAGAAUAGUGCCUCUAGUCCUCCCCGUUUCAAAACAGAGAAGAUGGAAAGUAAAACUGUUUUGCCCUUCACUGAUAAAUGUGAAUCCUCAAAUCUGACAGUAAACACAUCGUUUGGAUCAUGCCCUCAAUCAGAAACCAUUAUUUCAUCAUUAAAGAUUGAUGCCACCCUUACUAGAAAAAAUCAUUCUGAACAUCCGCUCUGUUCUGAAGAAGCCCUGGAUCCAGACAUUGAAUUGUCUCUAGUAAGUGAAGAAGAUAAACAGUCCACUUCAAAUAGAGAUUUUGAAACAGAAGCAGAAGAUGAAUCUAUCUAUUUUACACCUGAACUUUAUGAUCCUGAAGAUACAGAUGAAGAAAAAAAUGACCUAGCUGAAACUGAUAGAGGAAAUAGAUUGGCUAACAAUUCAGAUUGCAUUUUAGCUAAAGACCUUUUUGAAAUUAGAACUAUAAAAGAAGUAGAUUCAGCCAGAGAAGUGAAAGCUGAGGAUUGCAUAGAUACAAAGUUGAAUGGAAUUCUGCAUAUUGAAGAAAGUAAAAUUGAUGACAUUGAUGGUAAUGUAAAAACAACUUGGAUAAAUGAACUGGAACUGGGAAAAACUCAUGAAAUAGAAAUAAAGAACUUUAAACCAUCUCCUUCCAAAAAUAAAGGCAUGUUUCCUGGUUUUAAGUAAUAAUACUUAACUCUCAAGCUAAGUAAAAAUAUGUCAUCAUGCUUAUGUUAAACUCUGUUGUAAGUAAUAAUUUGUAAAUUGAAUAAGUGGCAUACUUUUUAAAAAACUAUUUUAUGUUCAGAAAUGUAAAUGUUAUUAUUCUUGAGUUUUUGGGUUUUUUUUUUUGAGACAGAGUCUUGGUCUGUUGCCCAGGCUGGAAUGCAGUGGUGUGCUCUGGGCUCACUGCAACCUUCACCUCCAGGUUCAAGUGAUUCUCCUGCCUCAGCCUUCUGAGUAGCUGGGACUACAGGUGUGCACCACCAUGCCCAGCUAGUUUUUGUAUUUUUAGUAGAGAUGGGGUUUCACCAUGUUGGCCAGGCUGGUCUCGAACUCCUGGCCUCGUGAUCUGCCCUUCUCUGCCUCCCUAAGUUGCUGGGAUUACAGGUGUGAGCCACAGUGCCUGGCCCAUUCUUGAGUUUUGAUAAAGUAAUUCAUACAAAGUACUGUCCUCAAAUAAGUCUUCCUUAGCUAAAUGCAAUUUAAAAUUAUUCAAAGAUCCUAGGGCACUUCUAGUUUCACGUAAAUAUUCAUAUUAGGUGGUUCUCUUCAUCCAUUUGUUUUCACACUGAUACAUAAAAAUUAACAGCAGUCUAAUCUAGUGACACCUCAGUCAUAUUUCGCUAUAGAUUUUACCUCAAAUCAGUCCAAGACUUUUUCAGAGAUCACCAUUUGUCUUGAAAGGUUUAUUUCGUUAUUAAACUGCCUACUUAUAAGUAAUUAAGAGAAAUUAAGAAAGUAGUAUGCAUUUUUAAUUGAAAUUGUUUUACAUUCUUUGUAUAAUAAACCUAAAACCAAACAUGUCAUAAACAAAUUGACGUAAAGAUAUAAAAUGCCAAAUGAAGUAUUCCAAAUUUUCUAUUCUAAUUAUUUAGCUUCACCAUCAUUGUGGAAAAAAAUACUAGAUCCUGCUUAGUAUUAUAUAUUUUUCCUAGUGGAUCAGUGAGUAAUAAGUACCAAACACUAGACUAGAAGGUAAUUUCUACAUUGUUUAGAAAGGGUGAAACAAUUUAUCCCCUCUGGUAUUGUUCUAGCAUAAGCUUUAGUUAUACAAUGAUUAAGAUAGAAAACUUCAUAUAUAAAUUUGAUAAGCAAACCCACAUUUAUAGCUGCAGCUAAAAUAUGUUUCCUUAGGGCACAGUAAUCCUUUCUGUGAAUUUUGACCUUGUUUGUGUUUUUGUGAAUGAAGCUAUAUGUCUAAUCAAAAAUGAUUAUAAAAGAGGCUCAUCUCUGACAUCAUUCCAAAAAUACAUUCAUUGAUCUCUUUUUAAGAAACAUCUGUUAUUCACUGGGCAUUGGGACUUUUUGUGAGUAAUUUGAAUUGAAAUUUUAUGAGCUAUCCAAGAAUUCUGUAUGGUCUAUUAUUUUCAAGUCAAAAUUUCCAGUAAGGAUUUACUUUACAUUUCAUUUGGAUAAAUGAAUCAUUAUAUAGGUAUGUCUUUGCUUCCAUUUUGAGACAUUUAGAUUUUUACAGCCUGUUUCUAUAGCAUUUGAUGUUACAACUCUAAGCGUAGUUCAAAGACAUUUAAAUUGACAAGUUACCAGUUAAAGAAUUUAGAAUAUAUUAGAUCCCAUCUAGUAUUAUAUAUUUUUUCUAGUUGAUCAUUGAGCAGUAAAUACCAAAUACUCGAUUAGAAGGUAAUUUUUACAUUGUUUUGAAAGGGUGAAACAAUUUAUCUCCUCUGGUAUUAUUCUUAAACCACAGAUAGGGAUAGUAGGGUAGUGAAACGAAUAAAUACCUGGUAGAAGACAAGAGACUUGGGCUCUACACCUGGCUCUGCCACUGAUUUGCUAAGUCAUAUUGGCAAUCACCACACCCUUCAGGGAAUUAGUUUCAUCUGUAAAAUGCAGCGGUUAGUACUAUAAAAUCAUACAAAUUUCUUUGUGCUUUGAGAAUCUAUAAAGGAAUGUCUGUUGAUAUUCUGAGUCGAUUUUCAUUUGCUUUUGUUCCAGAACGGUUAAAAUAAAGCAUAUUAUUUCAUUUAAAAAGUAAAGUGGCUCUUACUCAUUUACAUUUAGGGAACGAUGGUGACGUGGUUUGGCUAUGUCCCCAGCCAGAUCUCAUCUUGAAUUGUAGUUCCCAUAAUCCCGACGUGUUGUGGGAAGGACCCAGUGGGAGGUAAUUGAAUCGUGGGGGCGGUUACCCUCAUGCGGUUCUCGUGAUACUGAGUUCUUAUGAGACCUGAUGAUUUUAUAAGGAGCUUUUCCCUGCUUCACUCUCAUUCUUCUCUCCUGCUGCCCUGUGAAAAGUUGCCUUCCGCCAUGAUUGUAAGUUUCUUGAGGCCUCCUCAGUCAUGCAGAACUGUGAGUCAAUUAAACCUCUUUCCUUUAUAAAUUACCCAGUCUUGGGUAUGACUUUAUUAGCAGCAUGAGAACAGACUGACACAGAUGGUAUAUGUGCAUAAUAACUUGGAAAGCUAGAUAUUUAUUUUCGCAAUGCUACAAUUAAAACAUUUUGAGGACUUUUAAAAUUACCUUUAGGGCCAGGCGCGGUGGCUCACGCCUGUAAUCCCAGCACUUUGGGAGGCCGAGGCGGGCGGAUCACGAGGUCAGGAGAUCGAGACCAUCCUGGUUAACACGGUGAAACCCCGUCUCUACUAAAAAUACAAAAAAUUAGCCAGGCGUGGUGGCGGGCGCCUGUAGUCCCAGCUACUCAGGAGGCUGAGGCAGGAGAAUGGCGUGAACCCGGGAGGUGGAGCUUGCAGUGAGCCGAGAUUGCGCCACUGCACUCCAGCCUGGGCGACAGAGCGGGACUCCGUCUCAAAAAAAAAAAAAAAAAGAAAUUACCUUUAGAAUUGGUAAACUACAUGAGAAAAUUAAGCAUAUUAUUCAUAUCUUAGUGUUAUUACCCAACUUCAUCUCCAAUACUUUCCCCUUUCCCUAGCUAGAUAUGUUUUUGUUUGUUUGUUUUAGACAGUCUUGCUCUGUCGCUCAGGCUGGAGUGCAAAGGCACGAUCUUGGCUCACUGCAACCUCUGCCUCGCAGGUUAAAGCGAUUCUCAUGUCUCAGCCUCCUGCGUAGCUGGGAUUACAGGUGUACACCACUGCACCCAGCUAAUUUUUUUUUUUUUUUUUUUUUAAGUAUCGACAGGGUUUCACCAUGUUGGCCAGGCUGGUCUCAAACUCCUGACCUCAAGUGAUCUGCCCACCUCGGCCUCCCAAAGUGUUGGGAUUACAGGCGUGAGCCACCAUGCCUGGCCUAGAUAUUUUUUAUUCUUUCCAAAAUUUAAUUCUCCCUGAAGUUAAAAAUUUUCAUUACUGAGAAUGUACAUAGAGAUGUGUCACAACCCUUUAGUAAUUCCAAAAGGUGUUUCAAAAAUUUUAUACAAUGAUAAUCACUGUUGAAACAGGUGUAUAUUCUCCUCAGAUCAUGACUGACCAAGAUGAUAUUCCAAGAAGUAAACUACUGGCCUUUAUAGAGUAGGAUGUAGGCCAUUUUCAUUACUGAUAACAUACUUUUAAAAGAAAUGUUUACAGAUUUAAAUAAGUUAAAACAUCUAAAUGCUUUUAAAAGAGCACCUGGCACAUUGCAAGUUAUUCAUUAUUAAUUAGUAGAUGAAUCAUAUAUCUGGAGUGCACCCUUGCUCUAUAUGAAAGCUUCCCUAACUAUAGAUAUAUAGGUGAUAGACUGACAAUAAAGAUUUGAGGAAAGAAAAAUUAUUUGGCUGGCUUAUUUUUUAAGCUUUUGAGAUGUAUAAGGUAGAGAUUGUUUAUCAAAUAAUUUAUGUGACACAUUCAAUGCAUAUGAAAUAAUUAUCUAAUACUGAAUUUAUUCAAGGACUGAAAGUAUAUAGAGCACACAGGCUGCAAACCAGGAAAACUACCAGUUAGAGACAGGGCUUUAUUCUUGGAAUAAAGGUACAAUGUAAAGAGUAGAUGUUUCAUGACUUGAUUAAAUUAUUUAAAACUGUCUAGAAUUGUGUUAUAAAACUAUUACUAUGUUUCUAUGCACUUAGUUAUUACAUGGGUUUAAAUUUGGCACUGUUUCUAAGUUUCUAUAAGGCUUUGUUGUUAAGAUCUUUCUAUUCAAAACAUUAAUUUUAACAAAAAGCUUUUCCCCGUUAUUUUUCUGCAACUGGACUUUUUUGUAUUACUUUCCUAUAUUAAAACGCAUUUAAAAUA